GUGACGUGUCCCGCGCUUGGCGCAGCAGGAAGCGGCGGCGAACGCGGCCUGAAUUCCCGGCGCCGGCCCCAGCUCCUCUGCCGCUGCCGCCAUGCUCGACUUCUUCACCAUUUUCUCCAAGGGCGGGCUUGUGCUCUGGUGCUUCCAGGGCGUUAGCGACUCAUGCACCGGACCCGUUAACGCGUUGAUUCGUUCCGUGCUGCUGCAGGAACGGGGAGGUAACAACUCCUUCACCCAUGAGGCACUCACACUCAAGUAUAAACUGGACAACCAGUUUGAGCUGGUGUUUGUGGUUGGUUUUCAGAAGAUCCUGACACUGACAUAUGUAGACAAAUUGAUAGAUGACGUGCAUCGGCUGUUUCGGGACAAGUACCGCACAGAGAUCCAACAGCAAAGUGCUUUAAGUUUAUUAAAUGGCACUUUUGAUUUCCAAAAUGACUUCCUGCGGCUCCUUCGUGAAGCAGAGGAGAGCAGUAAGAUCCGUGCUCCCACUACCAUGAAGAAAUUUGAAGAUUCUGAAAAGGCCAAGAAACCUGUGAGGUCCAUGAUUGAGACACGGGGGGAAAAGCCCAAGGAAAAAGCAAAGAAUAGCAAAAAAAAGGGGGCCAAGAAGGAAGGUUCUGAUGGUCCUUUGGCUACCAGCAAACCAGUCCCUGCAGAAAAGUCAGGUCUUCCAGUGGGUCCUGAGAACGGAGUAGAACUUUCCAAAGAGGAGCUGAUCCGCAGGAAGCGCGAGGAGUUCAUUCAGAAGCAUGGGAGGGGUAUGGAGAAGUCCAACAAGUCCACGAAGUCAGAUGCUCCAAAGGAGAAGGGCAAAAAAGCACCCCGGGUGUGGGAACUGGGUGGCUGUGCUAACAAAGAAGUGUUGGAUUACAGUACUCCCACCACCAAUGGAACCCCUGAGGCUGCCUUGUCUGAGGACAUCAACCUGAUUCGAGGGACUGGGUCUGGGGGGCAGCUUCAGGAUCUGGACUGCAGCAGCUCUGAUGACGAAGGGGCUGCUCAAAACUCUACCAAACCUAGUGCGACCAAGGGAACACUGGGUGGCAUGUUUGGUAUGCUGAAGGGCCUUGUGGGUUCAAAGAGCUUGAGUCGUGAAGACAUGGAAUCUGUGCUGGACAAGAUGCGUGAUCAUCUCAUUGCUAAGAACGUGGCUGCAGACAUUGCCGUCCAGCUCUGUGAAUCUGUUGCCAACAAGUUGGAAGGGAAGGUGAUGGGGACGUUCAGCACGGUGACUUCCACAGUAAAGCAAGCCCUACAGGAGUCCCUGGUGCAGAUUCUGCAGCCACAGCGUCGUGUAGACAUGCUCCGGGACAUCAUGGAUGCCCAGCGUCGCCAGCGCCCUUAUGUCGUCACCUUCUGCGGCGUUAAUGGAGUGGGGAAAUCUACUAAUCUUGCCAAGAUUUCCUUCUGGUUGUUAGAGAAUGGCUUCAGUGUCCUCAUUGCUGCCUGUGAUACAUUUCGUGCUGGGGCCGUGGAGCAGCUGCGUACACACACCCGGCGUUUGAGUGCCCUACACCCUCCAGAGAAGCAUGGUGGCCGCACCAUGGUGCAGUUGUUUGAAAAGGGCUAUGGCAAGGAUGCUGCUGGCAUUGCCAUGGAAGCCAUUGCUUUUGCACGUAACCAAGGCUUUGACGUGGUGCUGGUGGACACGGCAGGCCGCAUGCAAGACAAUGCCCCUCUGAUGACUGCCCUGGCCAAACUCAUUACUGUCAAUACACCUGAUUUGGUGCUGUUUGUAGGAGAAGCCUUAGUAGGCAAUGAAGCCGUGGACCAGCUGGUCAAGUUCAACAGAGCCUUGGCUGACCAUUCUAUGGCUCAGACACCUCGGCUCAUUGAUGGCAUUGUUCUUACCAAAUUUGAUACCAUUGAUGACAAGGUAAACGUGAGACUGGAGGCUGGAAUGGGCGUCCUGCACAAAGGAGCUGAGGCUGCAAGGAAAUCUUGGCUCCAGCGCUUCCUGUUCCUGAGAGGCUUCAAAAUGCAUCUUACCUGAUGUACCCCUUGUGGAGAUCUCACAUGUCAGUCGCUUGAAAUAUUCUGGAAGAUCGGCAUAGUCAUCUCCAUAGGAGAUGACUUUAAUCCCCUUGUCCAGCAUGUUUUCUCGAAGCUUUUUGAACUCAUCUACGUCUCCUCUCCGAACCAGCAUGAAAUGUUCUAGGUCAGAUUUAUGCUUGACAGCCUCCAAGAAAAGGGCCUGGAAAGUGGUGUCAUCCACAGUCCAGCCACAGCCCAGGAAAAGAAAUGACUUGUUUUCGUAGAGUUUCUGAAUUUCUCUCUGGAAGGAAAAGAUACAACAUAUUGACAUUGUGAAGACACACUCAAGGCAAGUCUGAAACAAGAAGGUCAUGCUACGUUGAGCAGACUGUGAUGACCAAUUAAGCAAGACUUAAGUGGGUUGGUAUGUCCCAUCAAGGAGUGUGAUCUCUUGCUUAUUGCUGUAACUUGAUGAUUGGUCUAAAAUUUUAUCUUUACCUGCCAUUCUUCUGUAGGCUCUCUAAUCAGCGUUUCAUAGAGCUGGUGUCAGUGUACUGGUGCAGUAGUUUACUUCUUUAUUUUUUAUGCUUUAUAUAUUUUUUGAGACGGAGUCUCACUCUUUCACCUGGGCUAGAGUGUAGUGGUGUGACCUCGGCUUACUGCAACCUCCACCACCCUGGUUCAAGUGACUCUCAUGCCUCAGCCUCCCGAGUAUAUUACAAGUGUGCACCACCACACCCAGCUAAUUUUUGAAUGUUUAGUAGAGACGGGGUUUUGCCAUGUUGGCCAGGCUGGUCUGGUACUCCCGACCUCGAGUGAUCCACCCACCUUGGCCUCCCAAAGUGCUGGGAUUACAGGCGUGAGCCACUGCACUUGGCCAGUAGUUUACUUUUUUAUUUUUAUUUUAUUUUUGAGACAGAGUCUUGCUCUGCCACCUAGGCUGGAGUGCAGUGGCAUGGUCUUGGCUCACUGCAACCUCCUCUGCCUCCCAGGUUCAAGCGAUUCUCCUGCCUCAGACUCCCAAGUAGCUGGCAUUACAGGCACCUGCCAGCACGCCCAGCUAAUUUUCCUAUUUUUAGUAGAGACAGGGUUUCACCAUGUUGGCCAGGCUGGUCUGGAACUCCUGACCUCAUGUGAUCUGCCUGCCUCAGCCUCCCAAAGUGUUGGGAUUACAGGCGUACUUUUUUAGAUUUAUGUGCCCAGAGGUCAUUGUGCAAAGAGUAGGUCUUCAUAUAUCUUAAUCCUUCCAUUUCUGGACCAUAUUUGCCUUUGUCUCACAAACUGAACUGUGAAUCACCAGAGAAGAUAAUUCCAUCAUCGGAUUUGCUCAAGGAAAGGCGUUUGAUACUUAGAACAUCAGUAUGUGUGUGUGUGUGUAUACAUAUACACACACAAAAACACAGAAAUGACUGCCUAAGGGAUCACUCAAUGUCAGAGAUGGAUGCAGUUAUGGCAGAUGUUGGGAAAGAAUGGGUAAAAAGAAAAAAAAGUCCCUUGUGCUUUAGACAAUACAUUUUCUCGGUCUUUUGCCUCAUUAUUAAAAGAUGCUAUAAUCUAUAUGACCCAGUCCUGAAAACAGCAAACAAGAUUCUUAGAGCUGGGGGCAGCGAAUACUUCUGGUUUGAACAUGUUUAUCUGAACAAGUCGAAAAUGUGCAUCCCAAAAGAUCAAUAAGCUUUUCACAAAGAGUAAGUGUGAAUAAAUGUGGUUAAUUCAA